CUCCACCUCCUGGGUUCAAGUGAUUCUCUUGCCUCAGCAUCCUGAGUAGCUGGGAUUACAGGCAUGCACCACAAUGAUCGGCUCCAAACAGGAGCAUCUUGGUAUGAUUUUUGUAGAGAAAAGAUGGCUAUCCCGCCCAAUGUUUGGCCCCCUCCUGCAAAGGCCAAAACAUUCGUUGGGUUUUUCCUUUACUGUCUAAAUAAAGAAGAAUUUGUGCACAGUCUGAGUGGGUCAGGAUUUCAUCCCAUGGCCAUGUGGGAGCUCCAAGAUUUGAUCUCCGGGCUGACCUGUGCAAGCAUCCUGCCUCAUUCCAUUUGGCUGAAGCUCCUGCUCCACUUCUUGCUGGGCUGUGACCAUUCAGGAUCCCCCACUGUCCACCAGAGUCAGCACCUAAAAGGAGAGAAAAUCUUUUUCUGUCUGGUGUUUUUCAAAAUUUUGAUGAUGGACUCACAUCAAGGAUGAAGAGCUUUGAUGUCAUUUGAACACCACCACCAUCACCACCACCAGCAUCAACAAACAAACAAGCAAACAAGCGUGAACUCAGGAGCCCUGUGGCCCAGCCUCCAGUCCAUUUCCUCACUGUGAUCUGGCUAAGUCACCUCCCCUCCACCUCAGUUCAGUCACCUACACAACAGGAAUGGUGGCUCCUGGCGUGAAAAGUUCUUAGGAGCAUUCAGCAUGAUGCUGUGUGGAGCACUUGGAAACUGCGUGUGCAUCACCUCAUAUUUCUGGCCACAGGUCAUUCAGACAUCUGCCCUUUGCCCUGGAGGAGAACCACUAGGGACUUGUGCCCAUAAGCACCAAUUCUGGCUUUUACCCUACCCAUCCUUUGCCAUCCCAAACUAUGCCAUCAACAAAUUCUAGAAAUCAAGUUAGAAAUGCUGUUCCCACGAGGGUCUCUGUGGUCUCUCAGAACAACAAUCAGCUGGCCCUGCUGGGCAGAUGUUGCCCAAUCCUAACCCACACUUAGCUAUCAACUUAAUCAUUCUCAACUAAAAACACCUACCUGAACACUUUUAGGGGUUAAGAAUAGUAUAAUCUCACUUAGCCAUUUGCAUUUUUUCUUCUUUUUACAAAAAGAAAUUUAUCUUUUUUUUUUUUUGAGACGGAGUCUUGCUCUGUUGCCCAGGUUGGAGUGCAGUGGCGCAAUCUUGGCUCACUGCAAGCUCCGCCUCCUGGGUUAGCGCCAUUCUCCUGCCUCAGCCUCCCGAGUAGCUGGGACUACAGGUGCCUGCCACCACGCCUGGCUAAUUUUUUUGUAUUUUUAGUAGAGACGGGGUUUCACCGUGUUAGUCAGGAUCGUCUUGAUCUCCUGACAUCGUGAUUCGCCCUCCUCAGCCUCCCAAAGUGCUGGGAUUACAGGCGUGAGCCACUGCGCUCUGCCAAGAAUAGUAUAAUCUCACUUAGCCAUUUGUAUUUUUUCUUCUUUUUACAAAAAGAAAUUUAUCUCAUUAUUAUGUUUAAUCAGUUUCUUGAGGUAUAACUUAAGUGUGCUAAAAUUUGCUCUUUUUAGUGUACAGGUCUAGGAUUUUUGAGAAACACAUAUUCAUAUGUGACCACCCCCAUGAUCAACAUAUGGAACAGUCAUUUGCCACCCAAAAUUACCUUGUGCCCUUUUGUUGUCAGACUCUUCUUUCUCCAGACCCUGGCAACCACUGAUGGAUUUUCUGUCCCUAUAGUUUUGCCUUUUCCAGAAUGUUCUGCAAAUGUAAUCAUUUAGUAUGUAGCCUUUUAAGUCUGAUUUCUUUCACUCUGCAUAAUGCAUUUGAGAUUCACCCACGUUGUUACCUGUUACAAUGGUUUGUUCCUUUUUAUUGCGGAGUAAUAUUCCCUUGCAUGGAUGUACCACAGUUUGGGUAACCAUUCAACAGUCAAAUGAGAUUGAAUUUGUUUCCAUUUUUUGGUGAUUAUAAAUACAGCUAUAAACAUUUGUGAAAGUGUUUUGUAUGUACAUACAUUUUUCUUAGACAUUUGGUUUUAAGAGAUGUAUUUAGGUUUAGUUCCAGAUGAACAAUGAGAGACUGAAAGACUUAAGGGACCCCUGAGAAGAGCAGAGGGAAUAUUCCCUGAGGCAGCCAUCAGUCAGACCUGGCCCUGUCAUUUAAAUGUGGGCUAGUGGUAGCAAGAUGCUGUUAUUAUUUUCACCAAGGACAUUUUUUGAGUAGCAAUUAAAAUGAAGUCUAUUUCUCUGAGCCCCUGGAGAAGAACAUAAGCACAUGAUGGUAACCAUCAAUUUAGUGGGCCUAACGUUAUCUAGGUGGUUAAUGUUUCCAUGGCUUCUGGCAAUUCCCAGUGUAAGUCACCUGUGUAUACUGGGUGGAUGCUUCUUUAAAUUAAAGAUAAGCUGUUCAGCUUAAUAACAGCUAAGGGAGAAUAUAGAGCCCGUGGGUGAACUGUUUACUAACAAGCUUCUUCAGGGUCAUUCAACUUGAAUGAACUCUCUUUUAGGCUAACUUGGUUUGUGGAGGGAAUGCAUGUUUCUUAGUUAAAAUAGUUACAUUGGAAUCCCAACUGUGCACAGGACUUCAAGGGUAAUUAUGAACCCCCACUGCAGAUUUCAGGCUUAGCACCAAUUCUCCUUGCUUUCUACUUGUAUCCAUCAAAAACAGAAGUUACGAUGGAGUUACAGCUAUACUUGUAAGGGUCUCAGUGAACCUCUCCCACUAUUCUGCCUUAUCACCUUUGGGUUCCUGUGUUCUCUACCCCCUCCCCACUGCAUGUUUUCAUUCAGCCAGGAAACAUUUACUGCCUGCCUGGUAUCAAGCCCUUGCAUGAGGGUGGGAGCUCAUAAAGAUGACUACACUAGAGAAUCAUUUGACCUUUCUCAUGUAGACCUCAACAUGAAUGAGUUUCAAUGCUGAUAGGGCAAUCAUUACCUUCAGACAAAUUUUCAGGAACAGCCAAGACUAGAGAAUGUAUGGCUAAAACACAGCACUAUGCAUUUAUAAUAGUCAUGGGUUCUCCUGUUUUAAUUGUACAUGGAGAAUAUUUCAGCUUUAUUUGUAUGGGCUGCUCUUAUGUAAAACAUUAUUUCAAUGAGGAAAUGUGUUUGGGGUUCUAAAUGACUAACUUACAAACACAACUUUGAAUAAAGUCCAUGAAUAAUUUGAGGAUUUAUGUCUAUCAAUGGCUGAUUUACCAGAUUGUUGGCUUUGGGUUUAUUGGUAUCCAUGUUGAGAGGCAUCAGAUCAUCCAAGGUUUAAGUUUCGUCCUGACCACUGACUAGCAUUGAGACCUUAAUGGGAUUAAUAACAAUGAUAAUGAUAGUGACAAGAGCUAGCUUUUCAUGAGCACAGUGGCUAAGAGAGUUAGCAUCAGUUCUAGCUGCUUUCAUUGACAUAGAUGUAAAUGGGGAGGGAAACCAUGACUAGACUCAAAUCUCUGCUCUAACGUCUGAUACCUGAAUAUCACUUUGCAAGCCACGUCAUCUCUCUAAGUUGUAGCUCUUUGUCUGAAAAAUGUGGAUAGUUAAUACAUUAUAAAUAAAUUAUUAUUACAUUAAUACACAGAAAUUCAUAAUGCUAUUGUGGGGAUUACAUGAGAUGAUGGAAGUAUUUAAUCUAGUGUCUUGUAUAUGGCAAAUAAAAAAUAAAUAUUCACUGCUGUUAA